AGACUACUCUCCCCCAUGGCGGACUUCGCUGGGCCGUCUUCUGCCGGCCGCAAGGCCGGGGCUCCCCGCUGCUCUCGAAAAGCCGCAGGUACUAAACAGACAAGUACUUUGAAACAAGAAGAUGCUUCUAAAAGGAAAGCUGAACUAGAAGCAGCUGUGAGAAAGAAGAUUGAAUUUGAGAGAAAAGCUCUACAUAUUGUUGAACAGCUUUUAGAGGAGAAUAUUACAGAAGAGUUCCUAAUGGAGUGUGGGAGGUUCAUUACACCUGCUCACUACAGUGAUGUCGUGGAUGAACGUUCUAUUGUCAAACUCUGUGGUUAUCCUUUAUGUCAGAAGAAGCUGGGAAUUGUACCAAAACAGAAAUAUAAAAUUUCUACCAAAACCAAUAAAGUCUAUGAUAUUACUGAAAGAAAGUCUUUUUGCAGCAAUUUUUGUUAUCAAGCAUCUAAGUUUUUUGAAGCACAAAUUCCCAAAACUCCAGUAUGGGUUCGAGAAGAAGAGAGGCAUCCUGAUUUUCAACUGCUAAAGGAAGAACAAAGUGGCCAUUCUGGAGAAGAAGUACAGUUAUGCAGUAAAGCCAUUAAAACAUCAGAUAUCGACAAUCCUAGCCACUUUGAAAAGCAAUAUGAAUCUAGUUCUUCUAGCACUCACAGUGAUAGUAGCAGUGACAAUGAGCAAGACUUUGUUUCCUCCAUUCUACCAGGAAACAGACCAAAUUCAACAAAUAUUAGACCACAGCUGCACCAAAAAAGCAUAAUGAAAAAGAAAGCUGGUCACAAAGCUAACUCCAAACACAAAGACAAAGAACAGACAGUAGUAGAUGUCACUGAGCAGUUAGGCGAUUGCAAAUUAGAUAGUCAGGAGAAAGAUGCUACAUGUGAACUUCCUUUACAGAAAGUAAAUACUCAGAGUUCUUCAAAUAGCACUUUGCCUGAAAGAUUAAAAGCGUCAGAAAAUUCUGAAAGUGAAUACAGUAGGUCAGAAAUAACUCUAGUAGGCAUAAGUAAGAAAAGUGCAGAGCAUUUUAAGAGAAAAUUUGCCAAAUCAAACCAAGUGUCUAGGUCAGUGUCUAGUUCAGUGCAGGUGUGUCCUGAAGUUGGAAAGAGAAACUUACUUAAAGUUUUGAAGGAGACUUUGAUUGAGUGGAAGACAGAAGAAACAUUGAGGUUUUUGUAUGGCCAGAAUUAUGCUUCUGUGUGUCUGAAACCCGAAGCCUCUCUGGUUAAAGAAGAACUUGAUGAAGAUGACAUAAUCUCAGAUCCAGAUAGUCAUUUCCCUGCCUGGAGGGAAUCUCAGAACAGCUUGGAUGAGUCUUUACCUUUUAGGGGCUCAGGUACAGCCAUUAAACCACUGCCAAGUUACGAGAAUUUGAAAAAAGAAACUGAAAAGUUAAAUCUGAGGAUCAGGGAGUUUUACAGAGGACGGUAUGUUUUGGGUGAAGAAACCACCAAAUCACAAGACUCAGAAGAGCAUGAUUCCACCUUUCCACUGAUAGACUCAAGUUCCCAGAACCAGAUUAGAAAACGCAUCGUACUUGAAAAGUUGAGUAAAGUGUUGCCUGGGCUUCUGGUUCCUCUUCAGAUUACAUUGGGAGAUAUUUACACACAACUUAAAAAUCUUGUUCGAACUUUCAGGUUAACAAAUAGAAAUAUUAUACACAAACCUGCGGAAUGGACUUUAAUUGCUAUGGUGUUGCUGUCAUUACUGACCCCAAUUCUUGGCAUUCAGAAACAUUCUCAGGAAGGUAUGGUGUUUACACGGUUUCUAGACACCCUCCUUGAAGAAUUACAUCUAAAAAAUGAAGACCUUGAAAGUCUAACCAUCAUAUUUAGAACCAGCUGUUUACCAGAGUGAUAUAUUCCAUGAAGACAAAAUAGAAGAUGAACUUCUAUUCACCGUUUCUGGAAUUCUAGCCGCCAUGAUGGUCUGGUGGUGACUGAUAACUAGUUUUAUUCCAAGACAUACCUUUACCUCUUUAAGUUUCAAUCUCCCAUCUCCCAGUCCUUCAGUCCCCAACUGCAGAGGAUGACCUCCCCAGAUAGAGGAGAAUCAUUACUCCAACAAGAAUAACCAAGUCUUUGUAUCCCUAGUACAAGACAUAGUAUUUUUAUUCGAAAAUGAAUGUUUAAGUAUUAAAUUGAAACUUGAAUGAAUAUUCAAGAAAAUAUAAUGAUCUCUACUUUUUCUGGAUGAUUUCCAGCCAUCAUAUCAGUUUGCCAAAAAAAUUGAGAAAGUUAUGAUUUUGACCUCCCAACCUAAACUCUAAAUUCUAAAGAUCAGUAAACAAUUAGGUCAAUAAAUACAUACAAUUUAAGAUGAAGCCCUUUGGAAGUCUAGUCCAAAACAGGAAAAUCUCAGAACUUUCUGGACUCAAGGAAAUGCUUUAAAUGGAAUCUGUAGUUUGUUUGCAGGAGAGACAAUUUCUAGAAUUUAGAUUGCUUUUCAAAAUGUUUAUCAGGUAGGCAAGUUAGCAGUUGAGGCGGAACACAGACAACUUGGGGAGCUUUACUGGAAGGCCAAGAAAAUACUCUUGGACACUGGAGGAAAUGACAGCUACUAAAGCCCAAUCAUGGAAAAGGACCAGAAAGCAGCCCACUGGAAUGGGGAGCUUAGUGGGCAAGGAGGUAGGGAUAUAAUUUCUCUUCUUGGCUCCACCAGUAAUUAGCUCUGUGGCCCAGUCACCUAAACUUUCUGGACUUCAGUUCAGGUUGUAUGGCAGUAGGCCAUAGAAUUGGCUACUGCCAUACAAUCUCUAUGGGAAAGGACUGCAAAAACUAAAUUUUAUCUCUGUAUGGGCAAAGGCUACUGUCAUCCUGUUGUUGGUCUGGGGCCACUCUGACAAUUUUUUUUAACCUCAUUUGAUUGUGUAAGGGUCUAACCACAACAAAAAAUCAUAGUGUAAUAGAAUUAAUCAAGUUCAGCAAGGUCACAGGCUAGAUCAAUAUACAGAAAAUCAAUUGUAUUUUUCUGUUCAGAAAACUCCAAAAAUGAAAUAAAGAAAAUUGUGUUCACAAUAUCACCAAAGAGAAUUAAAUACUUAGGAAUAAAUUUAACAAAAUAAGUAUAAGACUUGUAUAACGAAAACUAUAAAACAUUCAAGAGGGCUGGGCAUGGUGGCUCAUGCCUUUAGUUCUAGCACUUUGGAGGCAGAGGCAGGAGGACUGCUUGAGCCCAGGAGUUCAAGACCAGCCUGGGCAACAAAGUGAGACCCUGUCUCCACAAAAAAUAAAAAUAAAAAUAAAUUGAAGAUGGCCGAAUAGGAACAGCUCCAGUCUACAGCUCCCAGCAGGAUGGACACAGAAGAUGGGUGAUUUCUGCAUUUUCAACUAAAGUACCUGGUUCGUCUCACUGGGACUGGCUGGACAGUGGGUGUAGCCCACAGAGGGUUAGCCGAAGCAAGGUGGGGCAUCGCCUCACCUGGGAAGCGCCAAGGGGUCGGGGGAUUUCCCUUUCCUAGCCAAGGGAAGCCGUGAGUGACUAUACCUGGAGGAGGGGUACACUCCUGCCCAAAUACUGCUCUUUUCCCACAGUCUUCGCAACUGGCAGACCACGAAAUCCCCUCCCAUGCCUGGUUCAGUGGGUCCCACGCCCACAGAGCCUUGCUCACUGCUAGCGCCAGCAGUCUGAAAUCGACCUGGGACGUGGGAGCUUGGCGGGGUAGAGGUGUCCGCCAUUGCUGAGGCUUGAGUAGGCGGUUCUAUGCUCACAGUGUAAACAAAGCAGCAGGGAAGCUCAAACUGGGCAGAGCCCACCACAGCUCAGCAAGGCCUACUGUCUCUGUAGAUUCCACCUCCAGGGGCAGGGCAUAUCUGAACAAAAGGCAGCAGACAGCUUCUCCAGACUUAAACGUCCCUGCCUGACAGCUCUGAAGAGAGCAGUGGUUCUCCCAGCACCGCGUUCAAGCUCCGAUAAUAGACAGACUGCCUCCUCAAGUGGGUCCCUGACCCCCGUGUAGCCUGACUGGGAGACAUCUCCCAGUAGGCGCCGAAAGACACCUCAGAGAGGUAGAUGCCCCACUGGAACGAAGCUUCCACAGUAAGGAUCAGGCAGCAAUAUUUGCUGUUCUGCAGCCUCCACUGGUGACACCCAGGCAAACAGGGUCUGGAGUGGACCUCCAGCAAACUCCAACAGACCUGCAGCUAAGGGGCCUGUCUAUUAGAAGGAAAACUAACAGAAAGGAAUAGCAUCAACAUCAAAAAAAGGACAUCUACACCAAAACCCCAUCCAUAGGACACCAACAUCAGAGACCAAAGGUAGGUAAAACCACAAAGAUGGGGAGAAACCAGACCAGAAAGGCUGAAAAUUCCAAAAACCAGAAUGCCUCUUCUCCUCCAAAGGAACACAACUCCUUGCCAGCAAGGGAACAAAACUGGACAGAGAAUGAGUUUGACAAGUUGACAGAAGUAGGCUUCAGAAGGUCGGUAAUAACAAACUUCUCCAAGCUAAAGGAGCAUGUUCUAAUGCGUCGCAAGGAAGCUAAAAAUCUUGAAAAAAGGUUAGACAAAUGGCUAACUAGAAUAACCAGUGUAGAGAAGAGCUUAAAUGACCUGAUGGAGCUGAAAACCACAGUACGGGAACUUCGUGAAGCAUACACAAGCUUCAAUAGCCAAUUCGAUCAAGUGGAAGAAAGGAUAUCAGUAACUGAAGAUCAAAUUAAUGAAAUAAAGCGAGAGGACAAGAUUAGAGAAAAAAGAGUGAAAAGAAAUGAACAAAGCCUCCAAGAAAUAUGAGACUAUGUGAAAAGACCAAAUCUAUGUUUGAUUGGUGUACCUGAAAGUGAUGGGGAGAACAGAACCAAGUUUGAAAACACUCUUCAGGAUAUUAUCCAGGAGAGCUUCCCCAACCUAGCAAGGAAGGCCAACAUUCAAAUUCAGGAAAUACAGAGAACACCACAAAGAUACUCCUCAAGAAGAGCAACCCCAAGACACAUAAUUGUCAGAUUCACCAAGGUUGAAAUGAAGGAAAAACUGUUAAGGGCAGCCAGAGAGAAAGGUCAGGUUACCCACAAAGGGAAGCCCAUCAGAUUAACAGCGGACCUCUGGGCAGAAACCCUACAAGCCAGAAGAGAAUGGGGGCCAAUAUUCAACAUUCUUAAAGAAAAGAAUUUUCAACCCAGAAUCUCAUAUCCAGCCAAACUAAGCUUCUUAAGUGAAGGAGAAAUAAAAUCCUUUACAGACAAGCAAAUGCUGAGAGAUUUUGUCACCACCAGGCCUGCCUUACAAGAGCUCCUGAAGUAAGCACUAAAAUGGACAGGAACAACCAGUACCAGCCACUGCAAAAACAUGCCAAAUGGUAAAGACCAUCAACACUAUGAAGAAACUGCAUCAAUUAAUGGAUGAAAUAACCAGCUAGCAUCAUAAUGACAGGAUCAAAUUCCCACAUAACAAUAUUAACCUUAAAUGUAAAUGGGAUAAAUGCCCCAAUUAAAAGACACAGACUGGCAAAUUGAAUAAACAGUCAAGACCCAUCAGUGAGCUAUAUUCAGGAGACCCAUCUCAUGUGCAAAGACACACAUAGGCUCAGAAUAAAAGGAUGUAGGAAGAUUUACCAAGCAAAUGGAAAGCAGAAAAAAGCAGGGGUUGCAAUCCUAGUCUCUGAUAAAACAGACUUUAAACCAACAAAGAUCAAAAGAGACAAAGAAGGUCAUUACAUAAUGGUAAAGGGAUCAAUUCAACAAGAACAGCUAACUAUCCUAAAUAUAUAUGCACCCAAUACAGGAGCACCCAGAUUCAUAAAGCAAGUUCUACAAAGAGAUUUAGACUCCCACACAAUAUUAAUGGGUGACUUUAACACCCCACUGUCAAUAUUAGACAGAUCAACAAGACAGAAAAUUAACAAAGAUAUCCAGGACUUGAACUCAGCUCUGGACCAAGCAGACCUAAUAGACAUCGACAGAACUCUCCACCCCAAAUCAACAGAAUAUACAUUCUUGUCAGCACCACAUCACACUUAUUCCAAAAUUGACCACAUAAUUGGAAGUAAAGCACUCUUCAGCAAAUGCAAAAGAACAGAAAUCACAACAAACCGUCUCAGACCACAAUGCAAUCAAAUUAGAACUCAGGAUCAAGAAUCUCACUCAACUGCACAACUGCAUGGAAACUGAACAACCUGUUCCUGAAUGACUACUGGGUAAAUAACGAAAUGAAGGCAGAAAUAAAGAUGUUCUUUGGAACCAACGAGAACAAAGACACAAUGUACCAGAAUCUCUAGGACAUGUUUAAAGCAGUAUGUAGAGGGAAAUUUAUAGCACUAAAUGCCCACAAGUGAAAGCAGGAGUGAUCUAAAAUCAACACCCUAACAUCACAAUUAAAAGAACUAGAGAAGCAAGACCAAACAAAUUCAAAAGCUAGCAGAAGGCAAGAAAUAACUAAGAUCAGAGCAGAACUGAAGGAGAUAGAGACUCAACAAACCCUUCAAAAAAUCAGUGAAUCCAGGAGCUAGUUUUUUGAAAAGAUCAACAAAAUUGAUAGACCGUUAGCAAGGCUAAAAAAGAAGAAAAGAGAGAAGAGUCAAAUAGAUGCAAUAAAAAAUGAUAAAGGGGAUAUCACCACUGAUCCCACAGAAAUACAAACUACCAUCAGCGAAUACUAUAAACACCUCUACACAAAUAAACUAGAAAAUCUAGAAGAAAUGGAUAAAUUCCUCGACACAUACACCCUCCCAAGACUAAACCAGGAAGAAGUUGAAUCUCUGAAUAAACCAGUAACAGGUUCUGAAAUUGAGGCAAUAAUUAAUAGCCUACCAACCAAAAAAAGUCCAGGACCAGACGGAUUCACAGCCAAAUUCUACGAAAGGUACAAAGAGGUGCUGGUACCAUUCCUUCUGAAACUAUUCCAAUCAAUAGAAGAAAAGGGAAUCCUCCCUAACUCAUUUUAUGAGGCUAACAUCAUCCUGAUACCAAAGCCUGGCAGAGACACAACAAAAAAAGAGAAUUUUAGGCCAAUAUCCCUGAUGAACAUCGAUGCGAAAAUCCUCAAUAAAAUACUGGCAAACCGAAUCCAGCAGCAUAUCAAAAAGCUUAUCCACCACGAUCAAGUCAGCUUCUUCCCUGGGAUGCAAGGCUGGUUCAACAUAUGCAAAUCAAUAAACAUAAUCCAUCACAUAAACAGAACCAACGGCAAAAACCACAUGAUUAUCUCAAUAGAUACAAAAAAGGCCUUCAACAAAAUUCAACAGCCUUUCAUGCUAAAAACCCUCAAUAAACUAGGUAUUGAUGGAAUGUAUCUCAAUAUAAUAAGAGGUUAUUUAUGACAAACCCACAGCCAAUAGCAUACUGAAUGGGCAAAAGCUGGAAGCAUUUCCUUUGAAGACCAGCACAAGGCAAGGAUGCCCUCUCUCACCACUCCUAUUCAACAUAGUAUUGGAAGUUCUGGCCAGGGCAAUCAGGCAAGAGAAAGCAAUAAAGCAUAUUCAAAUAGGAAGAGAGGAAGUCAAAUUGUCUCUGUUUGCAGAUGACAUGAUUGUAUAUUUAGAAAACCCCAUCGUCUCAUCCCAAAAUCUCCUUAAGCUGAUAAGCAACUUCAGCAAAGUCUCAGGAUACAAAAUCGGUGUGCAAAAAUCACAAGCAUUCCUAUAUACCAAUAAUAGACAAAGAGCCAAAUCAUGAGUGAACUCCCAUUCACAAUUGCUACUAAGAAAAUAAAAUACAAAGCACUGCUCAAGGAAAUAAGAGAGGACACAAACAAAUGGAAAAACAUUCCAUGCUCAUGGAUAGGAAGAAUCAAUAUCAUGACAAUGGCCUUGUUGCCCAAACUGAUUUAUAGAUUCAAUGCUAUCCCCAUCAAGCUACCACUAACUUUCUUCACAGAAUUGGAAAAAACUACUUUAAGAUUCAUAUGGAACCAAAAAAGAGCCCACCUAGCCAAGACAAUCCUGGGCAAGAAGAACAAAGCUGGAGGCAUCACACUACCUGACUUCAAACUUUACUACAAGCCUACAGUAACCAAAACAGCAUGGCACUGGUACAAAAACAGAUAUGCAGACGAAUGGAACAGAAUGGAGGCCUCAGAAAUAACACCACACGUCUACCACCAUCUGAUCUUUGACAAACCUGACACACACAAGCAAUGGGGAAAAGAUUCCCUAUUUAAUAAAUGGUGUUGGGAAAACGGGCUAGCCAUAUGCAGAAAACUGUAACUGGACCCUUUCCUUACACCUUAUACAAAAAUCAACUCAAGAUGGAACAAAGACUUAAACGUAAGACCUAGGACCAUAAAAAUCCUAGAAGAAAACCUGGGCAAUACCAUUCAGGACAUAGGCAUGGGCAAAGACUUCAUGUCUAAAACACCAAAAGCAAUGGCAACAAAAGCCAAAAUUGACAAAUGGGUUCUAAUUAAAGAGCUUCUGCACAGCAAAAUAAACUAUCAUCAGAGUGAACAGGCAACCUACAGAAUGGGAGAACAUUUUUGCAAUAUAUCCAUCUGACAAAGGGCUAAUAUCCAGAAUCUACAAAGAACUUAAACAAAUUUACAAGAAAAAAGCAAACAACCCCAUCAAAAAAUGGGCAAAGGAUAUGAACAGAUACUUCUCAAAAGAAGACAUUUAUGCAGCCAACAGACAUAUGAAAAAAUGCUCAUCAUCACUAGUCAUUAGAGAAAUGAAAAUCAAAACCACAGUGAGAUACCAUCUCAUGCCAGUUAGAAUGGCGAUCAUUAAAAAUCAGGAAACAAUAGAUGCUGGAGAGGUUGUGGAAAAAUUGGAACGCUUUUACACUGUUGGUGGGAGUGCAAAUUAGUCCGACCAUUGUGGAAGUCAGUGUGACGACUCCUCAAGGAUCUAGAACUGGAAAUACCAUUUGACCCAGCAAUCCCACUAUUGGGCAUAUACCCAAAAGAUUAUAAAUCAUUCUACAAUAAAGACACAUGCACACGUAUGUUUAUUGCUGCACUAUUCACAAUAGCAAAGAUUUGAAACCAACCCAAAUGCCCGUCAAUGAUAGACUGGAUUAAGAAAAUGUGGCACAUGUAUACCAUGGAAUACUAUGCAGCCAUAAAAAAGGAUGAGUUCAUGUCCUUUGCAGGGACAUGGAUAAAGCCGGAAACCAUCAUUCUCAGCAAACUAUCACAAGAUCAGAAAACCAAACAACGCAUGUUCUCACUCAUAAGUGGGAGUUAAACAAUGAGAACACAUGGACACAGGGAGGGUAACAUCACACACCAGGGCCUGUGGGGGGUGGGGGGCUAAGGGAGGGAUAACAUUAGGAGAAAUACCUAAUGUAGGUGACAGGUUGGUGGGUGCAGCAAACCACCAUGGCAUGUGUAUACCUAUGUAACAAAACUACAUGUUCUGCACAUGUAACCCAGAACUUAAAGUAUAAUAAAAAAAAUAAUUAUUAAAUUUUAAAAAACUAGCCAGGCAUGGUGCUGCACACCUGUAGUCCCAGCUACUUGAGAGGCUACAUUGGGAGGAUUGCCUGAGCUUGGGAGGUUGAGGCUGCAGUUAGCUGUGACUGUGCCAGUGCACUCCAGCCUGGGCAACAGAGCAAGACCCUGUCUCAAAAAAAGAAAAAGAAAAAUUCAGAGAGAUUAAAGAAGGUAUCAAGAAAUGUAGACACAAUCCAUGUUCAUGAAUUGGAAGAUCAAAUGUUGUUAAGAUAGCAGUUCUCCCCAAAUUAAUCUACAAUGCAAUCCCUAUCAAAAUCACAGCAGGCUUUUUUGAAAAAUUGACAAGCCAAUCUUAAAAUCUGUAUGAAAACAUAAAGGAUUCAGAAUAGCCAAAAUAAUUCUGAAAAUGAAGAAAUAAUUCUGAUCCAGAACUUACUACAAAGCUACAUUAAUCAAGACAGUGUGGUACUGAUAUAAAGAUAGGCAUACAGAUCAGUGGAACAGAGUCCAGGAAUAAACCUUCACAUUUAUGAUCAAUUAAGUUUUGACAAAAAUCCCAAUGAAAUUAUGGAGAAAAGAUGGUCUUUUCAACAAAUAGUGCUAGGAUAUUUGGAUAUCAAAUGCAGAAGAAAUUAAUUUAGAUUCUUACCUCCUACCAUAUGCAAAAAUAAACUCAAAAUUGAUCACACACCUACAUGUAAGAGCUAAAACUAUAAAACAUGUAGAAGAAAACAUGGGAGAAAACCUAGAUGACCUUGGUUUAGGAAGAAUUCUUAAGACACUAAUAGCACAAUUCAUAAAAGAAAAUAUUAAUAAAUUGGACUUCAUUAAAAUAUAAAAUUUUGUUUCAAAAAACUAUUAAGAAAAUUAAUUGGCCCGGGGAGGUGGUUCACAUCUGAAAUCCCUGCACUUUCGGAAGCCAAGGAGGGUGGACCACUUGAGCUCAGGAAUUUGAGACCAGACUGGACAACAGAGCAAAAUGCCAUCUCCACAAAAAAUACAAAAAUUAACCAGGCAUGGUGGCGUGCUCCUGUAGUCCUGGCUACUCAGAAGGCUGAGGUGGGAGGAUCUCUUGACCCUGGGAGGCAGAGGUUGCAGUGAGCCAAGAUCACACCACCGCACUAGAGCCUGGGUGACAGAGUGAGACCCUGUCUCAAAAAAAAAAAAAAAAAAAAAAAUUAAUUGAAAAAUCACAGACUGGGAGAAAAUAUUUUCAAACCAUAAUAAGUAUCUGAUAGAGGACUUGUAUCUAGACUAUGUAAAGAAUUCUUAAAACUCAAAAAUAAGGCAGACAACUUAAAAAUGGACAAAAUGUUUGAAUAGAUAUUUCAGCAAAGAUAUACAAAUUGCUUAGCAUAUGAAGAGAUGUGUACUAUCACUAGUCAUUAGGAAAAUACAAGUUAAAAGCAAAAUUAGAUACCAUUUUGGACCCACUAAAAUGACUAUAAUAAAAAAGACAGACAAAGAUAUGUGUUGGUGAUGAUGUGGAGAAACUGGAGCCCUAAUGCAUUGCUGGUGGGAAUGUAAAAUGGUGCAGCCACUUUGGAAAACAGUUUGGCAGUUUCUUAAAAAGAUAAACAUAAGUUUACCAUAUGAUCCUGCUAUUCCAUGAGAAGAGAAGUGGAAAUGUGUUCACAUCAAGACUCGUAGGCAAAUGUUCAUAGCAUUAUCAUUCAUAUUAGUCAAAAAGUGGAAACCAAAUGACCAUCAACUACUGGAUUUUUUUUUUUUUUUUAAGAGAUGAGGCCUCACUAUGUUGCAUACUCUGAAGUCAAACUCCUGGGCUCAAACAAUCCUCCUGCCUCAGCCUCCUCAGUAACUGGGACUGCAGGCAGGCACCAACAUACCCAGAUUAUUUCUUUUUCUUUUUUUUUUUAACUGGUGGAUUUCUUUAAAUGAUAUAUGUAUACAAUGGAGUAGUGAUAUAGGCUACAAUAUGGAUGCAUCUCAAAACAUUAUGCUUAGUGAAAGAAGUCUGAUGCAAUAUCCCACAUAUGGUAUGUUUCCAUUUACAGUCCAGAAAAGGCAUAUACUAAAUUAGCAGUUGCAUGGGUCUGAUGUGAAAACAUGGAUUGCCUGCAGAUGGGCACAAGGGAUCUUUUGGGGGUGACAAAAAUGUUCCAAAACUAAGUUGUAAUUUUUGCACAACUUUUAUGUGUGUGUGUGUGUGUGUGUGUGAGAUGGAGUUUCACUCUUGUUGCCCAGGCUGGAGUGCAAUGGCGCGAUCUCAGCUCACCACAACCUCCGCCUCCUGGGUUGAAGCAUUUCUCCUGCCUCAGCUUCCUGAGUAGCUGGGAUUACAGGCAUGUGCCACCAUGCCCGGCUAAUUUUGUAUUUUUAGUAGAGACAGGUUUUCUCCAGGUUGGUCAGGCUGGUCUCGAACUCCUGACCUCAGGUGAUCCUCCUGCCUCGGCCUCCCAAAGCGCUGGGAUUACAGGCGUGAGCCACCACACCCAGCCAUUUUUGCACAACUUUAUAAACUUUAAAAAUAAUUGAUUUAUGCACUUAAAACAGGUAAAGUUUAUGUGUAUAAAUUAUACCUUAAUAAAGCUAUUAAAAGUCAAAGAUUAUAACAGGGCCUCUCUCUCUCUGACCUAGUGACCUAGGGUAAAGAGAAAAAGAAGCUAGCCAGGCACAGGGGCUCACACCUGUAAUCCCAGCACUUUGGGAAGCCAAGAUGGGCUGAUUGCUUGAGUCCAGGAGUUUGAGACCAACUUGGGCAACAUAGCAAAACCCUGUCUCCACCAAAAAUAAAAAAAAUUAGCCAGGCAUGGCGGUGUAUGCCUGGAGUCCCAGCUACUCAGGAGUCAGAGGUGGGAGGAUCACUUGAGCCCAGGAGGCAGAGGUUGUAGGGAGCCAAGAUUGCACCACUGCACUCCAGCCUGGGUGACAGAGCAAGACACUGUCUCAAAAAUUAAAAAUUAAAAAAUGAGGGAAGCUGCUGUAUCUCCACUUCUUCCCUCUCUGUGCCCAGAGAUAUCUCUUCAGUUAUCUCACAUGCCCUACAAGUCUAGAGACCUCAGGUGAGGAGCCAGUAGCUCAGUAUAGAAACUAAGGAUCCAAGUGGACAACUGCCACCAAGUCACCACAGGGCCAGCUGCUUUGGGAGGGUGCUGCAUCUGCCUCCCAUACACUUCUGCCAAGUUUAUGUUAGUUUGGGAGGACUGAAGCAGAAUUCAGUUCAAAGUACUGUGCUGGAUUUUGGUUUCUAAAUAUUUUCCAAUAGAAAAGAACCCAGGCUUCUUGAGAAAAUAGCUAGGUUCUAAGGCUAGAGCCAAAAAAAUGCAAGAUAAGCCUGGAGCAUCUUGUAGUACCAGAAACUAAGCAAGUGCUCAAAAACAAAAGGAUAGAAGCAUGUCAGACAGACACAGGAGCCAAUCUGAAAGAGCUCCCUGGCCGGGCACGGUGGCUCACGCCUGUAAUCCCAGCACUUUGGGAGACUGAGGUGGGAGGAUGACUUGAGCCCAGGAGUUUGAGACCAGCCUGGGCAACAUAGGGAGACCCCAUCUCUACAAAAAAGUAAACAAUUAGCCGGGCAUGGUGGCACACGCCUAUAGUCCCAGCUACUCAGGAGGGUGAAGAUCACCUGAGACCAGGCGGUCAAGGCUUCAGUGAGCCAUGAUUGUGGCACUGCACUCCAGCCUAGGCAAUAGAGUGAGACUGUCUCAAAAAAUAAAAUUUUAAAAUAACUGAAGAGUAUAACUGGAUUGUUUGUAACACAAAGGAUAAGUGCUUAAGAUGAUGGAAACCCUAUUUAUCCUGAUGUGAUUAUUACACAUUGCAUGCCUGUACCAAAAUAUUUCAUGUAACCCAUAAAUAUAUACAUCUACUAUGUACCCACAAAAAUUAAAAAAUGUUUACAGGAGUGAACCACCGCACCUGGCCAGUGGAGUCUUUUUAAGGUAUUAUUUAGCAUCUUCUGCUUAUAGUCAUGUCCAAAAACCAGUUGAUCUUCCUACUCAUUAGGGGACAAGAUCAAUUCUCUAAAAAAUUAACCUAGCCCAAGGUAAGUGGUACUAUUCUGAAAUCUGAAAAUCUUUAGUAGCCUCACAUUAUAAGCCCUUCGUAGAAAAAGAAAAGUAAGCAUUUCUAGAAGCACAUUUUUGUUGGACUGAGGGUGGGGCAAGGAGCAGGGGUGACUUUCAUCUGAAAUGUACCUAGGCAGGCCAGAGUCUGAGUUAGGACUGGCUCCUGGGACUUUGCCAUCCAGGCCAAGAAGCAUGCUCCAGUGUGCAUGCACUCUCAUCAAAGCCCUAGUCAGGAAUCCCAGCCACUCCUCUCCUGUGCAGCACAAGCUGAAGGAUAAGGUGUGGGGCAGUGACUGCGUGGGGCUGCCUGUGUGAUUCCUGAUAAAGAAAUGCCUUCAUGAAAUGUAUUGUUCCCCAAUAAAGCUCAUUUUCUGUGAGAAUUCAUGUGUCCUUUUCCAAAUUAAACUAGCAAAAUAUGAACUUUUGUAAAAGGUCCACACCCAGCCAGUUUUCUACUCUCUAAAUGUUCAGGCCUUUGCCUGUCCUUCCCUCAGCAAAAAUACUGUGUUUUGGAAAACAUUACCAAUAAAGGAGCUGGGAGGUGGAAUUGGAUCAAAAUACCUUUAGAUGAAAGCAGCAGCACAAGCCAUUCCCUUUAAAUGAGCUGGCCUCACCUCUGGGGCCUAUGAAGAAAAGCCUGCUUCAAGGUGAUAGUUUUCAUUUUGCUUCCCAGCACCUCUGCAGUCAUAACCAAAGUGAAGGACAAUAUUGCAUGACUUCAGAAGAAAGCCAUCCAGCCACCUUGCAACAUGUUCAGGAAAUUCUGGACUCCCUUGGGGCUUGCAAAACUCCCUAUGUCUUGCAGACCAAAAGCAAGUUCUCAGUCACCUAGCUCUAGUUUGCAUAAUUAAAGAAAGUGGAAGCUGGUUCUUUUCUGGGUGACCCUUCACCCAACCAAGCUCAUAAGGACUUGUGACAAAAAUAAGAGCAAUAAAAUGAAGUUUUAACAGUGAAAACUUCUAUCACUUAGAUAAGCAGGAAAAGCCAGUCCCCUAGAUGCCCAUCUGACCCUACCUUACUGGGGUCAUACAGCCAAAGCAGUGUCCACUUCAGGUACUGUAAUGUUUUGAAGUUGACACAUAUAAUUUAAUGUAGUUUCAUGUCAUAAGUUAUAAGACUUUUCAGAGAAACAAUUUAGUAAUAUCUUCUGUAAUACCCAUCUUCAUUUUUUAUAUGAAAAAGCAUAGCCUAUGAUCUGUCACCUUGCUCACUCCCACAUCCUUACCUCUUAUCCUUCUCACAUCGUCCCAUUAACACAUUAUCCAUCUUUGGGGGGAAAAAAUACACUAAAUUUUAGACAGAGUCACUUUCACUAUGGCCACAAUGGGAGAAAAGACAGUCCACCUUCAAAGUCAACCAGAAUGACUCUUAACCUCUCUUGUCUGGGUUGGGCAUCCAGAUAAGAUUUUCUUCGUACAAAGAGUCUUGCUACUAGGAAAAAGAGUUUGAAAAUCACUAGUCUAACUAAAUAUCUCACUUUAAAAAAAGCACAAACUAAGACUCAAUGAGGUUUAUCUUCCACAAGAUCAGCCAGUUUUAGCAGAGCAGUUGCUAAAACCCAGGUCUCAAACUCCUUGUCUAUGGCUCAUCUAACUAAGCAACAAAAAGCCCAAUGAGCUCUGGAGAGAGAGAGGGAGCUAAAACAGGACUCAAUCAAAACCCACUUGGGAUUAGGGAAGCCACCCUCUGUGAGUGAGUUAAACUGAGAUUCCCUCCCCUUCACCCUGGCUUCCUUUGCAGAACAAGGGUCACCGCCAGAGGGAAAGCUGAGUUUACGGAGGGGAUCCUGGUUGGAGUCAGAGUAUACCUUGGUUUGGUUUUGUGGGGUUUUUUGAGACAGGGUCUCACUGUCACCCAGGCUGGAGCACAGUGACAGUCAUAGCUCACUAUAGCCUCAGACUCCUGGCCUCAAGCGAUCCUCCCACCUCAACCUCCAGAGUAUCUGGGACUAUAGGCACGUACCACCAUACCCAGCUAAUAUUUUUUUUAAUUUUAUAUUUUUUAGAGACAGGGUGUCACUAUGUUACCCAGGUCUCAAUCACUAUGUUACUCCUUGCCUCAAGCAAUCCUCUCACCUUGGCCUCCCAAAGUGCUGAGCUUACAGGUGUCAACCACUGUGGCCAGCCACGCAUUGGUUUUAAGGUCCAGAAUUUUUCUGUUUGGAGCCUUCACAAUUAGUUUUAGGUUGGGAGACCGUGAACCCACCAAGCAGCCCUUUAGAGGCUGGAAAAAGAGUUUGGAAAAAGAACUCUGUGGCUUUAGGAAUUUCUCUCGGAAAUCCUCUAGGGCAGAGAAGGAAAAUUUACCAAAUGGGAGAGUGUAUUAGUCUAUUCUUACAUUGCUAUAAGGAAAUACCCCAGACUGGGUAAUUUAUAAAGGAAAGAGUUUUAAUUGACUCACAGUUCCACAUGGCUGGGAAAGCCUCAGGAAACUUACAAUCAUAGCAGAAGGCAAAGGGGAAGAAAGGCACCUUCUUCACAGGGCGGCAGGAAGGAGAAGUGCAGAGCAAAGUGGGGCAAAGCCUCUAUAAAGCCAUCAGAUCUCAUGAGAACUCACUAUCAUGAGAACAGCAGGGGAGAACCACCCCCAUGAUCCAAUCACCUUCCACGAGGUCCCUCCCCCAACACGUGGGGAUCACAAUUUGGAUUACAAUUCAAGAUGAGAUUUGGGUGAGGACACAGAGCCGGACCAUAUCAGAGAGAAAGCUAUUACUGAAGACCUUUCUAACUCACUUCUGUAAAGAUCAAUUCAAUAAAAGCAGCAAACACACAUACUUUGCUUUCCUUGUGAUUAAUGCCUUGACUUUUUUGUGGAAAGUAACACCCCAAGAAAGCCAGCUACUCAUGUUGGCAAUAAAGGUAAAAGUAUCUAUGGAAUAAGGACCAUUUUUAGGACAAUACUUUCCCUACUACUUAGUUCUAGUCCCUUUUUUGUAGAAUUCUGAGGACUUUCUACAUACACAAUCAUGUCAUCAGCAAAUAAAGAUUAUUGUACUUGUUCUUUGCCAACCCAUAUGUCUUGCCUUACUGCCCUGGUUAGGACCUUCAGAACAAUACUGGAUAUAAGUGGUGAAAGCACAUAUCCUCCCCUUGUUCCUAAUUUUAGAGGGAAAGUACUCAGUCUUUCGCCAUUAAGUACAAUGUCAGCUGUAAGUUUUCCUAGAGACCCUUUCUCAGCUUGAAGAUGUUCCCUGGUAUUCAUAGUUUGCUAAAAGGUUUUUGUCAUUUUAAAUCAUAAAUGGGUGUUGAAUUUUGUCAAAGGCUUUUAAUGCAUCUAUGGAGAUGAUCCAAGUUUUUUUCCUCCUUAUUUCUGCUAAGGUUGUAUAAUUAUGCUCAUUGGUAUUUUAAAUGUUAAAUUAACCUUGCGUUCCUGGGAUAAGACCCACUGAUCAUGAUGCAUUUUCCUCUUUGUAAAUUGCUGUAUUCAUUUUAGUUUCUUCAGGAUUUUGCCUAUGUUUGAAGGAUAUUGGUUUGUAAUUUUUCUUGUAACAUCUUUGUCUGGUUUUGAAAUCAAAGUAAUACUGGCCUAAUAAAAUGAGUUGGAAUGUG